GGCGCUGAGAACGCGGGUCCACGCGUGUGAUCGUCCGUGCGUCUAGCCUUUGCCCACGCAGCUUUCAGUCAUGGCCUCCGGUAACGCGCGCAUCGGAAAGCCAGCCCCUGACUUCAAGGCCACAGCGGUGGUUGAUGGCGCCUUCAAAGAGGUGAAGCUGUCGGACUACAAAGGGAAGUACGUGGUCCUCUUUUUCUACCCUCUGGACUUCACUUUUGUGUGCCCCACCGAGAUCAUCGCGUUCAGCAACCGUGCAGAGGACUUCCGCAAGCUGGGCUGUGAAGUGCUGGGCGUCUCGGUGGACUCUCAGUUCACCCACCUGGCUUGGAUCAACACCCCCCGGAAAGAGGGAGGCUUGGGCCCCCUGAACAUCCCCCUGCUUGCUGACGUGACCAGACGCUUGUCUGAGGAUUACGGCGUGCUGAAAACAGAUGAGGGCAUUGCCUACAGGGGCCUCUUUAUCAUCGAUGGCAAGGGUGUCCUUCGCCAGAUCACUGUUAAUGAUUUGCCUGUGGGACGCUCCGUGGAUGAGGCUCUGCGGCUGGUCCAGGCCUUCCAGUACACAGACGAGCAUGGGGAAGUUUGUCCCGCUGGCUGGAAGCCUGGCAGUGACACGAUUAAGCCCAACGUGGAUGACAGCAAGGAAUAUUUCUCCAAACACAAUUAGGCUGGCUAACGGAUAGUGAGCUUGUGCCCCUGCCUAGGUGCCUGUGCUGGGUGUCCACCUGUGCCCCCACCUGGGUGCCCUAUGCUGACCCAGGAAAGGCCAGACCUGCCCCUCCAAACUCCACAGUAUGGGACCCUGGAGGGCUAGGCCAAGGCCUUCUCAUGCCUCCACCUAGAAGCUGAAUAGUGACGCCCUCCCCCAAGCCCACCCAGCCGCACACAGGCCUAGAGGUAACCAAUAAAGUAUUAGGGAAAGGUG